GACUGCAGGCAAACCCGGCGACAGCGCAGCUCGCGUCGACCCUGGCUCCUCUGCCUGCCCCCUCAGGCCCCCGCCUCCUUCAGGAUGACGCUGGACGUGGGGCCGGAGGAUGAGCUGCCCGACUGGGCCGCCGCCAAAGAGUUUUACCAGAAGUACGACCCUAAGGACGUCAUCGGCAGAGGAGUGAGCUCUGUGGUCCGCCGUUGUGUUCAUCGAGCUACUGGCCACGAGUUUGCGGUGAAGAUUAUGGAAGUGACAGCUGAGCGGCUGAGUCCUGAGCAGCUGGAGGAGGUGCGGGAAGCCACACGGCGAGAGACACACAUCCUUCGCCAGGUCGCCGGCCACCCCCACAUCAUCACCCUCAUCGAUUCCUACGAGUCUUCUAGCUUCAUGUUCCUGGUGUUUGACCUGAUGCGGAAGGGAGAGCUGUUUGACUAUCUCACAGAGAAGGUGGCCCUCUCUGAAAAGGAAACCAGGUCCAUCAUGCGGUCUCUGCUGGAAGCAGUGAGCUUUCUCCAUGCCAACAACAUUGUGCAUCGAGAUCUGAAGCCCGAGAAUAUUCUCCUAGAUGACAAUAUGCAGAUCCGACUUUCAGAUUUCGGGUUCUCCUGCCACUUGGAACCUGGCGAGAAGCUUCGAGAGUUGUGUGGGACCCCAGGGUAUCUAGCGCCAGAGAUCCUUAAAUGCUCCAUGGAUGAAACCCACCCAGGCUAUGGCAAGGAGGUCGACCUCUGGGCCUGUGGGGUGAUCUUGUUCACACUCCUGGCUGGCUCGCCACCCUUCUGGCACCGGCGGCAGAUCCUGAUGUUACGCAUGAUCAUGGAGGGCCAGUACCAGUUCAGUUCCCCCGAGUGGGAUGACCGUUCCAGCACUGUCAAAGACCUGAUCUCCAGGCUGCUGCAGGUGGAUCCUGAGGCACGCCUGACAGCUGAGCAGGCCCUACAGCACCCCUUCUUUGAGCGUUGUGAAGGCAGCCAACCCUGGAACCUCACCCCCCGCCAGCGGUUCCGGGUGGCAGUGUGGACAGUGCUGGCUGCUGGACGAGUGGCCCUAAGCACCCAUCGUGUACGGCCACUGACCAAGAAUGCACUGUUGAGGGACCCUUAUGCGCUGCGGUCAGUGCGGCACCUCAUCGACAACUGUGCCUUCCGGCUCUACGGGCACUGGGUAAAGAAAGGGGAGCAGCAGAACCGGGCGGCUCUCUUUCAGCACCGGCCCCCUGGGCCUUUUCCCAUCAUGGGCCCUGAAGAGGAGGGAGACUCUGCUGCUAUAACUGAGGAUGAGGCCGUGCUUGUGCUGGGCUAGGACCUCAACCCCAGGGAUUCCCAGGAAGCAGAACUCUCCAGAAGAAGGGUUUUGAUCAUUCCAGCUCCUCUGGGCUCUGGCCUCUGGCCUCAGGCCCACUAAUGAUCCUGCUACCCUCUUGAAGACCAGCCCGGUACCUCUCUCCCCACUGGCCAGGACUCUGAGAUCAGAGCUGGGGUGGAAGGGAGCCAUUCUGAACGCCACGCCUGGCCCGGUCAGUGCUGCAUGCACUGCAUAUGAAAUAAAAUCUGCUACACGCCAGGGAGAACAGGUGUCCUGUGUCUGUCUGGCUUGGGCAGGAAAGCCCAGAAGGUGCUCAGCAGGGUGCAGGGAUGGUGCCAUUCUGGCCCAGACCUUUAUUGGGGAAAAUGUUGGGGGUCACUUGGUCUUGCUCUUGCCUUUACCCGGAGGUAGCUGGAAGGGCCGCUCUAGUGCAGUCAACUUGCUGCUGAGCCUUUCCUCGCUGGCCUUGAGCCGCUCCUCCACCAGCCCCUGGAGCUGCUCCAGCUCUUUGUUCACUUGGGUCUUGAUGUAGGCUCGGAGGACGUGGAUGUGGCCUGCAGGGGCAGGGAAGAAGGGGCAGGGUGAGGAGAGAUGCUGUCUGGCAAUGGGGGGAUGGUCCCUAGUUGGGCAAACAGUCCCCAAAUUUCCCCUGGUGGGGAUAUAGAGGUAGCAAUGUUGUUUCCCUUUAGGAAAUGUUAGCAAGCCCUUGUGUGAGAGGUAGUUGGGUAGGGUGGCUAUGCUGGACUUUGCAGCUUCAAAUUCUGAUCCCUACUCAGUAGCUGUGUGACCUUAGGCAGGUUAUUUAACCUAUCUGUGCCUCAGUUUCCUUGUAUGAAAUGUGGAUAGUGAUACCUAGCACAUAGGAUUGAGGGAGGAUUAAAUGAGUUAAUUUAUGUAAAAUGCUUAGAGCAGGGCAUGCACUGCACACCUAUUGCCAAGUAUGUGCUGGCUGUUAUUGUCAUUGGCUUUCUCUUUUUUUUUUUUUUUUUGAGAUGGAGUCUUGCUUUAUCCCCCAGGCUGGAGUGCAGUGGCAGCGAUCUCAGCUCACUGCAAGCUCUGCCUCCCAGGUUCAUGCCAUUCUCCUGCCUCAGCCUCCCAGUAGCUGGGACUACAGGCACCCGCCACCACGCCCGGCUAACUUUUUGUAUUUUUAGUAGAGACGGGGUUUCACAGUGUUAGCCAGGAUGGACUCGAUCUCCUGACCUCGUGAUCCGCCUGCCUCAGCCUCCCAAAGUGCUGGGAUUACAGUUGUGAGCCACUGCACCUGGCCUGUUCUUUGUUUUUUUUUAACUCUUAAGUUCUGGGAUACGAGCAGAACAUGCAGGUUUGCUACGUAGGUAUACAUGGGCCAUGGUGGUUUGCUUUACCCAUCAACCCAUCAUAUAGGUUUUAAGCCACCGUCAUUGGCUUUCUAAUGAUCAUUUCUCUGGAGCCACUUCAGCUGUGCUUUUUGUUUGUUUGUUUGUUUGUUUUGAGACAGAGUCUUGCUCUGUUGCCCAGGCUGGAGUGCAGUGGCCAGAUCUUGGCUCACUGCAGUCUCCACCUCCUGGGUUCAUGCAGUUCUCCUGCCUCAGCCUCCUGAGUAGCUGGGACUACAAGCGCGCACCACCAUGCCUGGCUAUUUUUUGUAUUUUAGUAGAUAGGGGGUUUCACGGUGUUGCCCAGGCUGGUCGCGAACUCCUGAGCUCAGGCAAUCCGCCUGCCUCAGAUUGUGCUGGGAUUACAGGUGUGAGCCACCACGCCUGGCCUGCAGCUGUGCUUUUAUCUGUCAUCUUGGACUUCUGCAUAAGGGAUCAUUUAGAGAAAGGACUCUGACUAAAAACAAAAAGUCUGAAGUCCUGAUGUCAUCCAAACCCUUCAUUCUACACCUGCUCAGAGGGACAGGGCAGCCUGCCCUCUCCAGAUCCUCACUUGGCUCUGGCUCUGGUGGGGCCACUGUCUCUAGUUCCUCUUUCUGCGGGGUAACUGCCUGCUCCUCCAUCUCCUUGCUUUCUUCUUUCUCUGCAAACCAGAAGCAGGAAGAGACUGUGGCCCCAGGCCUGGCCCAGCCCAGCCCUGCCCUGGCACUCUCCCUUACCCGUCUCACUCUCUGGCCACAGUUUGGGUGGCUGUAGCCCCAUGUAAGUCAAAGACAGAUCCAGCCGCACCUGGGAAGCAAGGCAGAGGGAGGCUGAAAGGAGUGCACCUGUGCUGAGGGGAGGGGCGGUUGAGGGUGGCUCCUCAUGGUCCACCACCCCCUACCUGGGGUGUGAAGACGUAUUUAUAGAGCUUGAAGUGGCGGAAGUAAGUGUUGACCACGUAGUCUUCCAAGGCCAGCAGCUGUUCCUCUUUGAAGAGGUCGAUGCUGAAAGGAGGCCGCUGUGGUGGUGACUCGGAAUUAGAACCCUGACUACCUUCCGGAGCCCUGGCUUUGCCUCCAAAAGCCCAGCAACAGGAGCAAGGAGAGCCCACUGGGGUCUUCACAAGAAGAUAAGGGUGAUGAAUGUGAGAGAGACUGGGUGAGACCUUGUCUGGGGAUGGGUAAAGUUUCCAGAAUGUUCCAGGGGAACUGACCCUGACUCCAUGGCAAAAAAGGACACUGGUGAAGUAGCGGUAGCACUCCUCCACGUUGCCCAAGGGGGUUGCUGGUAGGGAAAGCAAGAUGCAGCAGUGAGGCCCUCUCUGGUAUCCAUUCAUUCACUUCACUCAACAGCUGUUUAUGACCAUGAGCUUCAGAAGCAGACAGAUCUGGGUUUCAGCACUGGCUUGUUUCCUUAACUCAUGUAACAAAUACUGAAUACCCACUAUAUGCCCACUGUAUGGUUUUCGGCACUGAACAAGACAGACAAGGUCCUGCCCUUACGAAGCUUAUAUUCUAGGGGAAUAAACCAAGAAAUAGAUCAUUUCAGCUAUUAAACAUUCUGAAGCAAGAGCUAUUAAACAUUCUAAAGCAGGUGUUAUUGUGCACUAUGCAUAUAUUUGCAUAUAUUAUUUCUCAGAACAGUCCUGUAAAAUGUGUGCUGUAUCCUUAAUUUCUAGAUAAGGAAGCAGUGGAUUGGAAAGCUGAUGGCUUGUGUAUGAUGAUGCUACUAAUAAUGACAUAUUCCAGGCAGAAAUCCCCUGCUUCUGCUUCCCAUGGUCACUUGUGCCAGGCCCGGUUCCUCUUCUCCCUGGGGCUCAAACCUGGUAGCUGCCCCCUCUCACCAAUACAAGCCUUGUGAAGAUCCUGGAGCAGGGCACAAGCCGCUGACGUCUGCUCCAGUGAGAAGCCCUGCUGGCGGCAGAAAAUGAGCGCGUGGCAGAAGAGGUCCAGGGUGAUGGCGUCCCUCAGGCUCUGCUCAGGACACCCUAGCUCCAGCAGCUCAGCCAGCACCCUUGGGAGGGAGAGAGGAGUGAGUGACAACUGGGCCUCCUUUCAUCACCCUACACCCACCACAUGCUUUGGAGUCAGCCAUUCCUCAUGUUUUCCCAACCUGACCCCUCAGCCUUUGCCAAGAGCUCUUCCCACGCCCCCCUCAGUCCCUACUCCCUCAUCUCAGCAUUGGUGGUCUUCUCCAGCUGGUGCAUGGAAUGGACGUCCAGGUACUUCCUGUUAUAGUAAAAGAAAAAGAGUAUUGGUGGCCGUUACCUAUCAUGACAAGGCUGUGACAGCUAGUGCGUGAGACUGGGAGUUGGCCACCGGCGUGAAGCUGGGCUCUUUUGCCAGCUUGCUGUGUGACUAUGCAAAUCGUUAACUCUCUGGGCCUAAAUGAACUCUUAUGAGCCUCUCCAUUUCUAAAGCCUAGGGUUAGGAAUCUUGAAUUCUUUUUUCUGCUCUGCCACUACCUUGUAUGACCUUGGUCAAGUACUCCCUGUGGCCCUCAGUGUCCCCCUCUGUACAAUACUCCUUAGCGGCCAUGAGACUCCAUUUACAUUCUGUCUUUGGCUCUUUUUUUCUCACACUGCCUCCUCUUUGGACUGGAGAGGCUGGAAAGCCAACUUCCAGUCACCUGGAGUAAUUGCAUCUCCAGGCCUCAGUCUCAUCUGUAAAAUGGGGAUGCCCUGGCCACAGACAGGACUGUUGGGGAGACAAUAAAGAACGCAAAUAUUCAGUGUAA